GAACUCGCGGGAGCGUCACCGUCCUGCGACGCUUCAGAGGAUCCUUAGGCCUCAGUGGUCUUUGACCCCCGGCCCCAGGACCUGACCCCAAGGAAACCUCCGGGACCUGUGGCUGGAGAGGUGACCGCCAGGCAUCCGGGGAGCCUUUGGAGAUCUCGGCUUCCUUUUUCCCCCGCUGCUUGCCGGCGUGUCCUCGGGUGGACGCGGGCAGCCCGAAGGGGAGUUUACAGACGCUCCCUCACAUCGGGGACGCGGCUCCUUUAAGGGCGCUGCCCUGAGGAUCUGUGUUUGGUGAAAAGGAGCCAAAUUCACCUGCAGGGCAGGCGGCUCUAGCAGCUUCAGAAGCCUGGUGCCCUGGCGACACUGGACCUGCCUUGGCUUCUUUGAUCCCAACCCCACCCCCGAUUUCUGCUCUGCUGACUGGGGAAGUCAUCGUGCCACCCAGAACCUGAGUGCGGGCCUCUCAGAGCUCCUUCGUCCGUGGGUCUGCCGGGGACUGGGCCUUGUCUCCCUAACGAGUGCCAGGGACUUUGAACAUGUCGGGGAUCGCCCUCAGCAGACUCGCCCAGGAGAGGAAAGCAUGGAGGAAAGACCACCCAUUUGGUUUCGUGGCUGUCCCAACAAAAAAUCCCGAUGGCACGAUGAACCUCAUGAACUGGGAGUGCGCCAUUCCAGGAAAGAAAGGGACUCCGUGGGAAGGAGGCUUGUUUAAACUACGGAUGCUUUUCAAAGAUGAUUAUCCAUCUUCGCCACCAAAAUGUAAAUUCGAACCACCAUUAUUUCACCCGAAUGUGUACCCUUCGGGGACAGUGUGCCUGUCCAUCUUAGAGGAGGACAAGGACUGGAGGCCAGCCAUCACAAUCAAACAGAUCCUAUUAGGAAUACAGGAACUUCUAAAUGAACCAAAUAUCCAAGACCCAGCUCAAGCAGAGGCCUACACGAUUUACUGGUUAGUAGCAGCCCUGGCCCCGCUGGUGGCAGCUCCUCCCCGUCCCAGCCAAGGCCGCCUGGCAGGACGGGAGUGGAGGACACAGGCUCACCCUACGGACAGCCAGGGUCCACGCCUCUGUGGGGAAGGUCGGGGGGCAUAAACCCUGUGGGCAGCAGGCACCGUUGCACACCGUCUGCGGUGGGCAUGGAUGGCGCCGGAGCCGUGUCCCGGGGAGGGAGCAGGCCAGGUGACGGGCUGUCUUGGGCCACUGCCCCAGUGAGUUGUGGCCAGCUAGGAGGGGAAGGACCCUGGGCGUGGGUGCCAGAGGAGGCCAUGCUGAGAGGCCUCUCCACCGGCUCAGCCUCCCAUGGACCCCAGCCUCCCGCGCCGCCCUUGCUGCUUGUCCCCAUCCCCUCUACAACUUGGUUCCUUCUGUGGGGGGGCCCAGCCCAGCAGGGCUCAGUGACGUGAUGCUGUCACACGGACCCUGGGCUUCCACCCUGUCCCUGUGAGGUGCUGCUGUGGCUAGAAGGGUCCCCGUGGGCCUGGGGUCCUGUCUGCACCGAGGAGGGCCUGGUGUGAGUUAGGAUGCAGACGACAGCCAAACAGUGCUGGGGAAAGCAGGGAGGACCCUGCCCUGAGCAGAGGCCAUGCGCCCGCCUGUCCUGUUCCCUCUGCAGCUGUUCUGGGCAGGUCCAUAAGAAGGUGGGUUGGGGCCUCCGACCCCCCACUGCUCCGCCUGCAGCGUUGAGAAACCCAGCCCCAUCUCACCACGGGUCCCCACACCUCUGAGGGGGUCUCAGGGCCCCCAAUGGCCAGGGACCCAGAAGGCUCACCUGCAGCCACCCCACACAUCCCUGCCACUGUGGGCAUCAGAGGCCCUCUCCCUCCAGGGUGCAUCUCCUGGUCAGGAGGGGGGAGGCUGAGGGGUCCCGGUUGCCUUAGGCCCGGCCUGCACAGGUCGUGAGGAAAAGCACCUGGUUUCGGCCGGGCGCAGUGGCUCACGCUUGUAAUCCCAGCACUUUGGGAGGCCGAGGUGGGUGAAUCAUGCGGUCAGGAGUUCGAGACCAGCCUGGCCAACAUGGCGAAACCCUCGUCCCUACUAAAAAUACAAAAAAUUAGUUGGGCGUAGUGGUGGGUGCCUCUAAUCCCAGCUACCUGGGAGGCUGAGACAGGAGAAUCACUUGAACCCGGGAGGCGGAAGUUGCAGUGAGCCGAGAUCCUGCCACUGCUCUCCAGCCUGGCGACGGAGGAAUGCUGUCUCAAAAAAAAAAAAAGCACGUGGUUUUGGAGAGAUGUGUUUCUCCCUGGAUGCGGGCCCAGCCCAGGUGUCUGCAAGGUGCCCUCCCUGGUGGCCGAGGGUGGCACAGAGGCCCCAGGCAGGGAGCAAGUAUCACAGCAGCCACCCCAGGCUCAGCCUGGCUCCCCUGCAUGGUGGUGCACACCUGUAGUCCCAGCUAUUUGGGAGGCUGAGGUGGGAGGACUGCUUGAGCCCAGGAGGUUGAUGCGCAGUGAGUUGAGAUUGCAGCACCGCAAUCCAGCCUGCUUGACAAAGCGAGACCCUGUCUCAAAAAAAAAAAAAAACUCAUAGCCGCUCAGUCAGCCAAGCCAUUGCUGGAAGUGGCUCGUGGGACGUGGCGUGACCUGGGUUUGUGUGCUGGCCUGCUGUGCCCUAGGAGUCCGUGAAAUGCAUUCCCUUGGACAGGAAGCCACAGUGCUCGUGGGUGUCCACAUGGCCCUUGAGGCAGAAAAUGUUUUCUUUUUUUUUUUUUUUUUUUUUUUUAAACAGAGUCUCACUCUGUCGCCCAGGCUGGAGUGCAGUGGUGUGAUCUCAGCUCACUACAACCUCUGCCUCCUGGGUUCAAGUGAUUCUCCUGCCUCAGCCUCCCAAGUAGCUGGGAUUACAGGCACCCACCACCACACCUGACUAAUUUUUGUAUUUUUAGUAAAGACAGUGUUUCACCACGUUGGCCAGGCUGGUCUCGAACUUCUGACCUCAGGUGAUCCACCCGCCUCGCCUCCCAAAGUGCCGGGAUUAUAGGCAUGAGCCACCGUGCCUGGAAAAUGAUUUCUAGGCCAAGUGUGGUGGCCCAACACCUGUAAUCUCAACACUUUGGGAGGCCAAGGUGGGCUGAUUGCUUGAACUCAGGAGUUCAUGACUAGACUGGGCAACAUAGCGAGACCCUAUCUCUACAAAAAAUUAAAAAAUUUGCCAGGGGUGGUGGCUCAUGCCUGUAAUCCCAGCACUUUGCAAGGCCACUGUGGGACGUUACCUGAGCCCAGGAGUUGGAGACCAGCCUGGGCCACAUGGCAAGACCUGCUCUCUUUAAAAAAAAAAAAAAAAAAAAAAUUAAGCCGGGGAUGAUGGUGCAUGCCUGUAGUCCCAGCUAUUUGGGAGGCUGAGGUGGGAGGACUGCUUGAGCCCAGGUGGUUGAUGCUGCAGUGAGCCAAGAUUGCAGCCUGGGUGACAAAGUGAGACCCUGUCUCAAAAAAAAAAAAAAAAGCAUGCCGGGCGCGGUGGCUCACGCCUGUAAUCCCAGCACUUUGGGAGGCCAAGGUGGGCAGAUCACGAGGUCAGGAGAUUGAGACCAUCCUGGCUAACACGGUGAAACCCCAUCUCUAGUAAAAAUAAAAAAAAUUAGCCGGGCGUGGUGGCGCACACCUGUAACCCCAGCUACUCGGGAGGCUGAGGCAGGAGAAUGGCUUGAACCUGGGAGGCGGAGCUUACAGUGAGCCGAGAUCACGCCACUGCACUCCAGCCUGGGCAACAGAGCCAGACUCUGUCUCAAAAAAACAAAACAAAAGGCAAAUGUUUUCCUGCCUAGCCCUUAGAUGGUCUGCCAUCCCCAGCAUGGUGUGGGCGUGAGCUCUGUCUGGCCUGCACCCCAUUUGCCGACCAUCUCCAGAGCUGGGCUGUGGCUCCCAUCUGCGGCGUGGGCUGGGCAGGGUUGCAGUCCCCCGCCCCGUGUGACUCUCCCCAGCGUCUCCUGGGCUUGGUGCCUGCUGGGCUGCACUGUACACUUGCGUGCACGUAAACAAACGUUCUUUCUCCUACACACAUCCGCUUGAAAAGCACCCUUUGUGAAGCAUGUGUGCGGGUUUCAGAUCGUUUUUCCUGGGUUUCCUGGAGGCCUUGGACCGUGUUCCUGCCCUGGCAGGUGCCUUUUCUCGGGGCCUCUGCUUGGUCAAGGAAGAGCUGGGACGUGUAGCCACCGCCUCUGGUUCCUUCCACGCCCACCCAGCUGAGCUGCUCUGCCCUGGGGCCGGCUGGUGGCCCAAGGAGGGCGCUGGGGUCUGGGCUGCGGUCCAGGCCCUUGGCGUGGGUGGGGGUGGCACCGGCGCUGCUGCCGUCCUGGGCUGUUCCACCAUGCAGAGUGAGGCUCAGUGUCUCAGACCAGGUCCAAUCCUGGCGAGACUGGCAGGACUGCGACCCCAGGAGCCACCUCCAUAAAUGUCAUGGUGUUCCCCCAUCCUCAGGGUCACACUGCACCCUGUGACCCAUCAGCCCCUAGGUGCAGCCUCGGCCGCCCUCCCGCCCACCUGUUUUGCCCGGGCAGUGUGUGCCAUGCCACUCUCCUGGGCAGCUGCUUGCAGGCUGAGCCUCACUCUACCCAGCUCCAGACCUGUUCGCUGAUGCCCCUGCACUGCCCAGCUCGGGCACAACGCCUUCUCAACCAGGCCUGCCUUCCCACACCUUUGCCCCUGCGGCUGAGAGCCUCAUGGAAAAACCCUCCAGAAAUUGGUGUCUAUUUUUGGGAAUUAACAAAAACAGUGGCAAGCAGUCAGUGUUUUCAGUUUAUUAGGACUGUCCCCAGACCUACAGAAAAGAGAAGCUGCUGAUUACUAGUUAGGACCAGACUUGGCAUCGGCAACGAUGUUGCAGGCCCUGGCGUGGGCCCUCUGGGCCUGAGCCCUCCUCGCAGCCCUGCGGGACCCCUCUGUCCCCCUUGAACACCACGUUCACCCAGCGUGGGUUCCUCUCCUCCCUGCCCUUCUGCCCCCGUCAGACCACGGGACAGUCUCAGCCACGUCAGAGCCAGCAUGGGCUCCCCACCACGCAGGCCUCCCUGCUUCUCCGGGCUUCUGCUUCUGUUACUAUGACGAGCUCCACACUGCCCUCCCCCAGGAGGUCCCAUCCUGCAGCCUGGUCUGCCCAGCUGGCUCCGGGGCGAGCGUGAGGGCCAGGCAGCUCAGCCCUCUAACACGUCUCUUCUCUUUUGACCUCCUCAGCCAAAACAGAGUGGAGUACGAGAAAAGGGUCCGAGCACAAGCCAAGAAGUUUGCGCCCUCAUAAGCAGCGACCUUGUGGCAUCGUCAAAA